ACGACUUGCGUGGCCCAAAGCUGGAUGGUCGUCCGUCCCACCAUGGCGGGUGGGUAAAGGUUCUUUUCCUGGGCUGUGUCAUUCCACCCAGAGCAAGGGAUAAGCCUGUGAUAGCCGUAAAUCCGGAACCACUACCAAGGUGAAAGACCUUCAAGUUAAUUGUUGGAACCUGCGGCUCUAACACUUCCAGCAAAGCUACUUCUGUGAAAGCUGUGACGAGCAGAGGAAAUGGGACAGGAGAGGAGCUGAAUCCUGAGAUUGUAUCGCUAGGAGCCCCCAAAGUACGAUGACGGUCCUCGGGCCAGCAUGGGGGUGCAUUGGCACCAUGUAAGGAAAGGGGCCCUCCCGUGGCACCGUUGGAGUGGGGCGGUGUGGGGUUGUUCGGAGAGAAAAGUUUCCCAUGAGCUCUGUUUCAGCAAACGGCGAUGACCACUUCCGUGGCAACUAAACAGUCUUGCCUUCCUGCACGUGGACAUUUUUCUUCAUGCAUAUUUCUCUUGCAAAUGGUUCUAUUGUUUGUAUAACAGUAUUUCAUGAGCGGAGAAGAGUUGGAAGCAAAAAUCUGUUCAUGAGAAAUCCUUUAUUAAGCUCCUACUGUAUGCCAGGUACUUUGGGCUGCAGGUACAGCUGUGAAAAAAAACAGAGCUUGUCAGGAAGAUCGGAGGUGCCAAGUAGCAGAGAAAGCAUCCCCCAGCUCUGACAGGGAGACAGCACAUGUCUAAGGCCCACAAGCCUUGGCCCUACCGGAGGAGAAGUCAAUUUUCUUCUCGAAAAUACCUGAAAAAAGAAAUGAAUUCCUUCCAGCAACAGCCACCGCCAUUCGGCACAGUGCCACCACAAAUGAUGUUUCCUCCAAACUGGCAGGGGGCAGAGAAGGACGCUGCUUUCCUCGCCAAGGACUUCAACUUUCUCACUUUGAACAAUCAGCCACCACCAGGAAACAGGAGCCAACCAAGGGCAAUGGGGCCCGAGAACAACCUGUACAGCCAGUACGAGCAGAAGGUGCGCCCCUGCAUUGACCUCAUCGACUCCCUGCGGGCUCUGGGUGUGGAGCAGGACCUGGCCCUGCCAGCCAUCGCCGUCAUCGGGGACCAGAGCUCGGGCAAGAGCUCUGUGCUGGAGGCACUGUCAGGAGUCGCGCUUCCCAGAGGCAGCGGAAUCGUAACCAGGUGUCCGCUGGUGCUGAAACUGAAAAAGCAGCCCUGUGAGGCAUGGGCCGGAAGGAUCAGCUACCGGAACACCGAGCUAGAGCUUCAGGACCCUGGCCAGGUGGAGAAAGAGAUACACAAAGCCCAGAACGUCAUGGCCGGGAAUGGCCGGGGCAUCAGCCAUGAGCUCAUCAGCCUGGAGAUCACCUCCCCUGAGGUUCCAGACCUGACCAUCAUUGACCUUCCCGGCAUCACCAGGGUGGCUGUGGACAACCAGCCCCGAGACAUCGGACUGCAGAUCAAGGCUCUCAUCAAGAAGUACAUCCAGAGGCAGCAGACGAUCAACUUGGUGGUGGUUCCCUGUAACGUGGACAUUGCCACCACGGAGGCGCUGAGCAUGGCCCAUGAGGUGGACCCGGAAGGGGACAGGACCAUCGGUAUCCUGACCAAACCAGAUCUAAUGGACAGGGGCACUGAGAAAAGCGUCAUGAAUGUGGUGCGGAACCUCACGUACCCCCUCAAGAAGGGCUACAUGAUUGUGAAGUGCCGGGGCCAGCAGGAGAUCACAAACAGGCUGAGCUUGGCAGAGGCAACCAAGAAAGAAAUUACAUUCUUUCAAACACAUCCAUAUUUCAGAGUUCUCCUGGAGGAGGGGUCAGCCACGGUUCCCCGACUGGCAGAAAGACUUACCACUGAACUCAUCAUGCAUAUCCAAAAAUCGCUCCCGUUGUUAGAAGGACAAAUAAGGGAGAGCCACCAGAAGGCGACCGAGGAGCUGCGGCGUUGCGGGGCUGACAUCCCCAGCCAGGAGGCCGACAAGAUGUUCUUUCUAAUUGAGAAAAUCAAGAUGUUUAAUCAGGACAUCGAAAAGUUAGUAGAAGGAGAAGAAGUUGUAAGGGAGAAUGAGACCCGUUUAUACAACAAAAUCAGAGAGGAUUUUAAAAACUGGGUAGGCAUACUUGCAACUAAUACCCAAAAAGUUAAAAAUAUUAUCCACGAAGAAGUUGAAAAAUAUGAAAAGCAGUAUCGAGGCAAGGAGCUUCUGGGAUUUGUCAACUACAAGACAUUUGAGAUCAUCGUGCAUCAGUACAUCCAGCAGCUGGUGGAGCCCGCCCUUAGCAUGCUCCAGAAAGCCAUGGAAAUUAUCCAGCAAGCUUUCAUUAACGUGGCCAAAAAACAUUUUGGCGAAUUUUUCAACCUUAACCAAACUGUUCAGAGCACGAUUGAAGACAUAAAAGUGAAACACACAGCAAAGGCAGAAAACAUGAUCCAACUUCAGUUCAGAAUGGAGCAGAUGGUUUUUUGUCAAGAUCAGAUUUACAGUGUUGUUCUGAAGAAAGUCCGAGAAGAGAUUUUUAACCCUCUGGGGACGCCUUCACAGAAUAUGAAGUUGAACUCUCAUUUUCCCAGUAAUGAGUCUUCGGUUUCCUCCUUUACUGAAAUAGGCAUCCACCUGAAUGCCUACUUCUUGGAAACCAGCAAACGUCUCGCCAACCAGAUCCCAUUUAUAAUUCAGUAUUUUAUGCUCCGAGAGAAUGGUGACUCCUUGCAGAAAGCCAUGAUGCAGAUACUACAGGAAAAAAAUCGCUAUUCCUGGCUGCUUCAAGAGCAGAGUGAGACCGCUACCAAGAGAAGAAUCCUUAAGGAGAGAAUUUACCGGCUCACUCAGGCGCGACACGCACUCUGUCAAUUCUCCAGCAAAGAGAUCCACUGAAGGGCGGCGAUGCCUGUGGUUGUUUUCUUGUGCGUACUCAUUCAUUCUAAGGGGAGUCGGUGCAGGAUGCCGCUUCUGCUUUGGGGCCAAACUCUUCUGUCACUAUCAGUGUCCAUCUCUACUGUACUCCCUCAGCAUCAGAGCAUGCAUCAGGGGUCCACACAGGCUCAGCUCUCUCCACCACCCAGCUCUUCCCUGACCUUCACGAAGGGAUGGCUCUCCAGUCCUUGGGUCCCGUAGCACACAGUUACAGUGUCCUAAGAUACUGCUAUCAUUCUUCGCUAAUUUGUAUUUGUAUUCCCUUCCCCCUACAAGAUUAUGAGACCCCAGAGGGGGAAGGUCUGGGUCAAAUUCUUCUUUUGUAUGUCCAGUCUCCUGCACAGCACCUGCAGCAUUGUAACUGCUUAAUAAAUGACAUCUCACUGAACGAAUGAGUGCUGUGUAAGUGAUGGAGAUACCUGAGGCUAUUGCUCAAGCCCAGGCCUUGGACAUUUAGUGACUGUUAGCCGGUCCCUUUCAGAUCCAGUGGCCAUGCCCCCUGCUUCCCAUGGUUCACUGUCAUUGUGUUUCCCAGCCUCUCCACUCCCCCGCCAGAAAGGAGCCUGAGUGAUUCUCUUUUCUUCUUGUUUCCCUGAUUAUGAUGAGCUUCCAUUGUUCUGUUAAGUCUUGAAGAGGAAUUUAAUAAAGCAAAGAAACUUUUUAAAAACGUAGCCAGGUUCAGUGACUCAUACCUGUAAUCCCAGUGACUCUGGAGACUGAAGCAGAAGGAUCACUUGAGCCCAGGAGUUCAAGACCAGACUGGGCAACACAGGGAGACCCUGUCUCUAAAAAAAUUUGUUUGUAAGUAGCCAGACAUGGUGGUGCACACCUGUAGUCCCAGCCACUCAGGUGGCUGGAGCAGGAGGAUCCCUUGAGCCCAGGAUUUUGAGGCUGCAGUGAGCCAUGACUGCACCAUGUACUACAGCCUGGGUGACAGAGUGAGAGUGAGACUCUGUCUCUGAAUACACACACACACACACACACACAUACACAGAGAGAGAGAGAGAGAACUUCACACCAGUGAUCAUCAUUAUGGGUAAUUUUCUUUUCUUCUUCAUGUUUUCCUGUAUGUUUCAAAUGAUGAACAUAUAGAUUCCUUAAUAAAAAGGCAAUAGAAUAAA